CAAAUGCUCUCCCCAGCCCGGAGAGCCCUGUCCCCAUCGGCCACUCUGAGCUCGAGGCCUAAAGGGACAGUGAGGAGGACCCUGCCCAGGCUCUCCCGGGGUUAGGAGGGACAGAGUGUUCCAGGAGGAGGUUUGAGCUGAGCUCAGGCACAGGUCUCUCUCUCUCUCUCUCUGACACAAGCGCACACACACACACACACUUGCACCAUGGGGAGCCACCCCACCCCUGGGCUCCAGAGAACCACAUCAGCUGGGUACCGAUUGCCCCCCACCAGGCCACCAGCCUCGGUCUCCCCAGCUGCCCGGGGUGGCCCUAUGGCCAGCAGGGGUCUUGCUGGUGGCUGCCAGGCCCCCCAGGCUCUGAAGGCGCAGCGGGUGGCUCAGGGAGCUGCCUGCGAUGGCGUGCAGCAGGACCAGCUGUGGCGGGAGCUCCUGGAGGCCGAGCGGCGGGGCCAGCAGCGCUGGAUUCAGAACUGGAGUUUCCUGAAAGACUAUGACCCAAUGGGCAACAAGAAGGAGCCUGAGAAGUUGCCAGACCAUGUGCCUCUCUUUUCGGACACAGUUCCCAGUUCCACGAACCAGGUUGUGGGCAGCAGGCUGGACACACCCCUGGGACAGACUCUCAUCCGCAUGGACUUCUUCUUCACAGAAGGGGCCCGGAAGAAGAAGCUGGAGGACCAGAUGCAGCCCAUCUAGGAGCAAGGAGGGCUGGGCUGGCCUUCCCCAGGUGGGUGUGGGUGGGGACAAGAGACCCAGCCCACAACAGCACCAGUCAGCUCCCCACACAAGGCAGCUUGGGUCUGCACUGUCUGUAAGCUGCAGGACACUCUUCCAGGGGACCCAAGGGGUCACUCUUACACACUUUUUACACGUAAGAUUCAGAGGAGUCAGUAACUGGUCCACGGCCGUACAAUCCCCAGCCCUUCCAGCUUGGGAACUCAUGGGUGCCCCAUGAAAGGGACCCUGCAUUGUGGUCAGGAGCACUGAAUGCCUGGGUUCAAAUCCAGCUUGUGACCCUGAUGAGCUGUGGGACCUUGAGCUGGCUGCUGCAACACUCUGUGCCUCCGUCUCCCCUCCUGCGAUUCAGUGUGUUCACUCCUUGCAGCUGCUGUGACAAGUGAGCACAAACUGCAUAGCUUAAAACAACACAAACGUAUCAUCUUACAGCUCUGAAGAUCACAACUCUGACAUGGGUGACAUGUUGCAGAGCUGUGCUCUUUUAGGAGUAUCUGGGGAAGAAUCUAUUUCCACAUUUUUUCCAGUUUCUCAAGGCAGCCUGUAUUCCUUAGUUGGCAGCUCCUUACUCCGUCUUUGAAGCCAGCAUCCUAGCAUCUUCAAAUCAGUCUCUAUCGCUUGCUCUCUCCUGCCUCACUCCUUCAUCUUUUCUUUCUUUCUCUCUCUCUCUCUUUUUUUUUUAGAGACAGUGUCUUACUCUGUCACCUAGGCUAGAGGGCAGUGAUGCAAUUAUAAAUCAUUGUAGCCUUGAACUCCCGGGCUCAAGCAAUCCUCCCACCUCAGCCUCCCAAGUAGCUAGGGAUACAGACACAUGGCAACAUGCCUGGCUAAUUUUUUUUUUAUUUUUAUUCCAGACAGAGUCUCGCACUGUCGCCUAGGCUGGAGUGCAACAGUGUGAUCUUGGCUCACCGCAACCUCCGCCUCCUAGGUCCAGGCAAUUCUCCUGCUUCUGCCUCCUGAGUAGCUGGAAUUACAGGCAUGUGCCGCCAUGCCUGGCUAAUUUUUUGUAUUUUUAGUAGAGAUGGGGUUUCUCCAUGUUGGUCAGGCUGGUCUGAAACUCCCAACUUCAGGUGAUCCGCCUGCCUCAGCCUCCCAAAGUGCUGGGAUUACAGGUGUGAGCCACUGCGCCCGGCCAUGCCUGGCUAAUUUUUAAAAUUUUAUGUAGAGAUAGGGUCUCACUAUGUUGACCAGGCUGGUCUUGAACUUUUGGGCUCAAAUGAUCCUCCCACCUUGGCCUCCCAAAGCACUGGGAUUACAGGCAUCUGGUUUCACUUCCUCCACCUUUUAAGGACCCUUGUGAUUAUAUCACAACCUUUAUAUUUAAGCAAAAAAAUGCAGAAAAGGCUUAGUUCCUCUUUGUUGGUUAAAACACAAAUGGAUUCAUUCUUUCAAACAUCCGCAUUCUCCUCUUCUUCCUGGGUGCUCUGCCAGGCUGUGGUUUCCCUUGGUUUGGGUGGAGCAUGUGACAGAGCCAUGGCCAGUGGAAUGGGAGCAAAAACCCUAGGUCUCCCUUCCAGGCCUGGUCCAUGAGACACUCCAGGUAUUGGCUUGUUCUCCUUUCCCCAUCAGCUGAAGAAGGGAGAGGACUUGGAGGAUGCAGGGAAGAGAGGGGCACAAGAUGGAGGGAGCAUGUCAGGACCAAGCCUGGAGCCCUGAGUGAGCUCGUGGAGCAGAAUCUCCCGACACCCACACUGACACACAAACAAAAUAAACAAAAACUGGCCAAAACAAAAACAAUAGCCCACACUUCUAGGGUAAAGCAUUUUAAAUUUAUUUUCUCAACAACCCAAGAGAAUCAACAGGCAGGGAUUUCGUAUUCAUUUAAUACAGGCAAAACCUGAGAUUCAGAGAGGUGAAAUAAAAUCCCGAACAUACAUUAAUGCCAGGCCUCAAGCUUGAAGCCCAGUGUUCUCUGCAGGACCCCAGCCGUGGCCUCCAGAAAAGAGAGAAAAAUGGGGCAGGGGCUGAAAUGACUGCUCUGUCUUUGAUGCUUGCUUGGGUCUUAUUCGGCAGUAGCUAAAUGUCACUGUUAUUUGCAUGCAUUAACUCAUUUAAUCCUCUCAGCAACCCUAUGAGAUAGAUACUCCUAUAAAUGAGGCAACUAAAGCGCAGAGAGGUUAAGUCACUUGCCCAAGGUCACACAGCUGGCAAGUGGUGAAGCUGGGGUUCAGACUCAGCAGUUGAGUCUGGCUCCAAGGACUAUAUACUUAAGCAUUAUGCUAUAUGGGUCCCCUUUAAUCCUCAAUGAAUUGAUUCCCCCAAAUUUAGCAAAUUACAGGAUUUUUCUGCUUAAAGAAAGUCUCUUGAUUCUUGAGAAAGGAAAAACUGAUUUUUCCAAUCUCUGGGAUCCCUACUACCAUCAAGAAUAGAUCAUCGGUGUUUCCAGGAGUUACACAGGACAGGACACGUUAUUUCCAUGCAACAGCCCCUGUGUUUCAUGCCAUACCCUGGCCCUGAGCGACUGUGUGAUGGAGCAGACCAGGCCCAGUGUGACUUGGCCAGGAAGAGGCCCAACCCUUCCUACUUGGAUCUGGAGGCCACCGCCUUCUUUCUCAGUGUCUGACAUGGAAGCUGGGCUCCCUCUCCACUCUGAGAUCAUCAGCUGGGUAAAGGUCAGUGGCCAGGACAGCCAGGGGUCCUGGUCACAUCCUGGCUGCAUCCCAUGAAGGUCAAGUGCUCGUCCUUAGGCUGGGUGGGUACAAAGAUGCUGGAGGCUCCUUAAAGACCCAAUCUACGUUUUUGCCCUGAGCCUGCCUUAUAUUAUUCUCACACUCAAAAUAAAGAAGAUUUCCAUUUGAGGGAGGGAGAGGCACAAGAAAAGUCAAGGUUAAGGAUGGCUGCAAGUGGUCAGGCCUGUGCAGAGGGGAGAGAAUCACUGAGUGCCCUGGAGGGCAGUGAGGAGGGCCAGGGACCAGCGCCGGUUCUGCCACUCCUGGAAGCACAGCCACUUACAGACAAUGCAACCUAUAAGCACAGACUCUGGGCUUGGCACAUUACCCACAUUGUGUCUUUUGCACGUAUUAGAAUUGUCACCAUUUGAGAGGUUUGGAAACUAAGCCGAACACUUCAUUCAAUCUGGUCAGGGUCUCACAACUAGUGAAGAGCCAGGAUCCAUCUCAUGUGUGACUUCUCCAUGCUGCCUUCCCCGCUCCAGGCCUCAGUCUCCACAGUUAUAAAAUGGCGCGGGAGGGAAGAAGACAGAUUUAAGGGCAUCUCCAGCUCCAGGAUUCUCUUCUUUGAGCAUUCAGGGAGUACUGAAGAAGAAAGGGGUUUGAGUUCUUUUACAGAGUGCAUUAGUCAGCUGUGAUAAUGCUGUGUAACAAAACACCCCCUUCCUUGCUCACAGGUCUGCAUGUAGCUGGGGCUCAGCUGAUUUUGGCUGGGCUUGGCUAGACUUGCCUCCACACUUCAGGUUAGGUUCAAGUUUUUUGUGCAUGUCUCUCAUUCUCUUGGACUGAAAGCCUCCUGGGGCAUGUUUUUCUCAUGGCACAUCACAAGGGUGCAAGGGCCCAACAGAACUGUGCAGGCACACUGAUGGCUUCUGCAUGCAGAACUGCUUUCUGUACUCUGCAAUGACCUGUCAUCACGCCAAAUCCCUCACAACCAGCCCCACCCACCCUCUGCUCCUUGCCACAUCUGCCUUCUUUUCAAGAAGACGCCUGCUUCUAACCUUCCCCAUCUCACCCACUGGGAGCCCAGAAAACCAGGACAGAGGGGCAUCUGCAGUGAAGUCCCAAGGCCAGCCUUUCAGCUCGUUUGGGCCAGAACAAGGGAGGGUGGAUGGGCCAGGAGGUCAUGAAGAAGUGGGCACCAAGCCUGCAGGGUCAGUGCCAGCAAAAGGAAAUGGGGGCAUUACCUAUAAAGAGAUGGGCACUUGGAGACCAAGGGCCAGGAGACAGCAGGGCUUCAGGAAAGGAAGAAUCAAGACCUGAGAGCCAUAGCAAGCCUGGAGGGAUGCUUGCUUCACAUUUUUUUUUUUUUUGAGAUGGAGUUUCGCCAGCUUGUCGCCCAAGCUGGAGUGCAAUGGUACGAUCUCAGCUCACCACAACCUCCGCCUACCAGGUUCAAGCGAUUCUCCUGCCUCAGCCUCCUGAGUAGCUGGGAUUACAAGCAUGCACCACCACACCCGGCUAAUUUUGCAUUUUUAGUAGAGACAUGGUUUCUCCAUGUUGGUCAGGCUGUUCUCAAACUCCCGACCUCAGGUGAUCCACCUGCCUCGGCCUCCCAAAGUGCUGGGAUUACAGGCAUGAGCCACUGCGCCCAGCCAACUUUCCACAUGAUAAAAAAUGACUUCUAUCCACGGAAAGUACAAGGCGAGCCUGGAGCAACUUCCUGUGCCAGAAACUAAGAAAAAUUCAAAAAGUGAUGAAAAUAUGGAAAAGGGAUACAAGGACCAGCCUAAAUUUGGGACAAUAUGAGCAUCGAAAUGAAGAACAGUAAUAGGCCACCCUGACCACGCCCAUGCCCACCCCCAGCCAGUGCCACAAGCCCCACCAAAUAACAUUAAUAAUAAUAACAAUAACAAAUAAUCCAUGGGUUCAUACCAAUAAUUUUUUUAAAUUUUAAGUACUAAUGAAAACUCUUUUUUUUUUUUUUUUUUUUGAGAUGAAGUCUCGCUCUCGUCCCCCAGGCUGGAGUGCGAUAGUGCGAUCUCGCUCACUGCAACCUUCGCCUCCUGGGUUCAAGCGAUUCUCCUGCCUCGGCCUCCAAGUAGCUAGGAUUACAGGCACCCGCCACCAUGCCUGGCUAAUUUUUGUAUUUUUAGUAGAGACGGGGGUUCACCAUGUUGGCCAAGCUGGUCUCGAACUCCUGACCGCAGGUGAUCCGCCCGCCUCGGCCUCCCAAAGUGCUGGGAUUACAGACAUGAGCCACUGCGCCUGGCCAUGAAAACUCUUUUCUAUUGAAGAAUGCAGAAUAAAUGAUAACAGAAAAAUCAGCAUUUAAUGACUCAGCAAUAACUGACUUAGGCAAGAAUCAAUAAAAGACACUAAAACGACUGAGUGAAAGAUUCUUAGAGAACGGUAAAUGCUGAAAUCUAGAAGAUACUGCCUUAACCAAACUAUUAAGCCAAACCUCACCAAUAACAGGACAGCUGACACCGUGCUCCCCUGGUGUGGUUCACUGAGGACAACGCUACCUACUUACCUAGGAAGCACUCUUGCCAAAAAAAAAAAAAGUAACUAGAAUAUAAUCAGGAAGAAACUCCUGGCAAACCCAAAUUGAGAAAUAUUCUGCCAAAGAGUUGGCCUUGAUUCUUCAAAAAUGUCAAUGUCUGCCAGGCGCUGUGACUCACGCCCAUAAUGCCGGCACUUUGGGAGGCCGAGGUAAAAGUAUCGCUUGAGCUCAGGAGUUUGAGACCAGCCUGUACAACAUGCUGAAACCGCAUCUCUGCUAAAAAUACAAAAAAUUAGCCAGGUGUGGUGAUGCAGGCCUAUAGUCCCAGCUACUUGGGAGGCUGAGAUGGGAGAAUCACCUGAGCCCAGGAAGUCAAGGCUGCAGUGAUUUAUGAUCUGAUCACUGCCUUCCAGCCUGGGUGACAGAAUGAGACCCUAUCUCAAAAAAAAUUAAUUAAUUAAUUAAAAUAAAAUAAAAAUAAAAAAAGUCAAUGUCAUAAAAGACAAAGAAAGGCUGAAGAAGUGAUUCAGCCCGUGAUCCUUGACUGGAUCCUGGGUGAAAGCAAAAGCAGCUCUAAAGGACACUUUGCAGACUAAAUGUUAGCUAACACCAUUGUAUCAGUGAGAAAGUGCAGAGUGUGGUGAGUCCAUUGAGGCUCUGUAGAAGAAAGUCCUUGUUCUUUUUGUUUGUUUGUUUUUGAGACGGCGUCUCACCCCAUUGCCCAGGUUGGAGUACAAUGGCACAAUCUUGGCUCACUGCAAACCUCCACCUCCCGGGUUCAAGCGAUUCUCCUGCCUCAGCCUCCCGAGUAGCUGGGAUUACGGGUGCGUGCCACCAUGCCCAGCUAAUUUUUUGUAUCUUUAGUAGAGACGGGGUUUCACCAUUCUGGCCGGGCUGGUCUCGAACCUCGUGAUCCACUCGCCUCAACCUCCCAAAGUGCUGGGAUUACAGGCGUGAGCCACUGUGCCCAGCCGAAAGCCCUUGUUCUUAGGAGGUGUUUGCUGAAAAGUCCCAUGAUGUAUAUAACAAACUUGCAAGUGGCUUAACGAAAAAUUUGUGUUUAGGAUUUUUUUUCUUUUUUUUUUGAGAUGGAGUCUCGCUCUAUCACCCAGGCUGGAGUGCAGUGGUGCCAUCUUGGCUCACUGCAGCCUCCGCUUCCCAGGUUCAAGCAAUUCUCCUGCCUCAGCCUCCCGAGUAGCUGGGAUGACAUGCACCUGCCACCAUGCCCGGCUAAUUUUUGUAUUUUUGUAGAGACAGGGUUUCACCACAUUGGCCAGGCUGGUCUUGAACUCUUGACCUCAGGUGAUCUGCCAGCCUCAGCCUCCCAAAGUGCUGGGAUUACAGGUGUGAGCCACCGUGCCCGGUGGUUUAGGAAUUUUUUUUUUUAAUGAAGGUGGGGGAAUGGCCACUGUGAAAGAAAAAUAAAUCUCAACUCCAAAAUCACUAAGCUAAGGGAAAAGUCAAGCUGGGAACCUGCCUCCCAUUUUAAUUCCUGAAUAAGAUGGCUAUAAAGAUAAAACAGCUACAUGCCUCCCUCACAAUUUGCCCACAAGGAAAUUCCUUGUGGGCCUCAAGAUCUUUACCCUACUCAGGAUCAUGCCAAGAAUUAAAAAAAAAAACAAAAAACAAAACUUUACCCUGAAACAUUUCUGUUGAAUUCAUCCUGGCAAUGUAAACUGAUAGCUGAUCUUAACAGGUGCAGGACAGAAAAUCAUUCCUCUGCUCACCUGAGAGAAAUGCUUAUCUGAUUGCUUCCUCAGACCUACUGUGUAUGUAAAAAUGAAGAUUCACUGAGCCAGACUAGAUUGUGAAUUCACUGAAAGGCUGAUCAAGGACUCAAAAGAAUGCAAGCUUUUGUCUCUUAUCUACCUAUGACCUGGAAGCCCCCCUCUUCGAGUUGUCCUGUGUUACUGGAUGGAACCAAAGUAUAUCUUACAUAUAUUAAUUGAUGUCUCAGGUCUCCCUAAAAUGCACAAAAGCAAGCUGUACCCCAGCCACCUUGGGGACGUGUCGUCAGGACCUGUUGGCAAAAUAAACUUUUAAAUUGCUUGA